UGAAUCGGGAAAUGGCCGCUGUGUGGUUGCAACGGAGAUAAAUUCCCGUAACCGCGAUUCGGCGUGUCAGGAAUUCGAAUUUAGAGUUUAAUUUCUCAGAGCAUUCUCUCCAGGAAGAAUUUUUACAGUAUCUCAAAGACUUCACUUGACUUCUUGAUCCUGCAUAAACCCAAGGAGAAAAGAAAUGGGUCGCUCCAAUUCUAGAUCACAUUCUUCAAGGUCAAAGUCUAGAUCACAGUCUAGUUCUCGAUCAAGAUCAAGAUCUCAUUCUAGAAAGAAGCGAUACAGGUCUCGUUCCAGAACAUAUUCAAGGUCUCGUAGUAGAGAUCGUAUGUAUUCUAGAGAUUAUCGUCGUGAUUAUAGAAAUAAUAGAGCAAUGAGACGACCUUAUGGGUACAGAGGAAGGGGUAGAGGGUAUUAUCAAGGAGGAGGAGGUAGAUAUCAUCGAGGUGGUUAUAGACCUGUCUGGAAUAGAAGGCACUCUAGGAGUCCUAGACGAGGUCGUUCACGUUCCAGGAGUCCAAAAAGAAGAUCCGUUUCUUCUCAAAGAUCCAGAAGCAGAUCUCGCCGGUCAUAUAGAUCUUCUAGGUCUCCAAGAUCAUCCUCUUCUCGUUCUUCAUCCCCAUAUAGCAAAUCUCCUGUUUCUAAAAGACGAGGGUCUCAGGAAAAACAAACCAAAAAAGCUGAAGGGGAACUCCAAGAAGAGAGUCCGUUGAAAAGUAAAUCACAGGAGGAACCGAAAGAUACAUUUGAACAUGACUCAUCUGAGUCUAUCGAUGAAUUUAAUAAGUCGUCAGCCACAUGCGGUGAUAUUUGGCCUGGCCUUUCAGCUUAUGAUAGUCCUAGAUCACCCCAUAGUCCUUCACCUAUUGCUACACCACCUAGUCAGAGUUCAUCUUGCUCUGAUGCUCCCAUGCUCAGUACAGUUCACUCUGCAAAAAAUACUCCUUCUCAGCAUUCACAUUCCAUUCAGCAUAGUCCUGAAAGGUCUGGGUCUGGUUCUGUUGGAAAUGGAUCUAGUCGAUACAGUCCUUCUCAGAAUAGUCCAAUUCAUCACAUCCCUUCACGAAGAAGUCCUGCAAAGACAAUCGCACCACAGAAUGCUCCAAGAGAUGAGUCUAGGGGCCGUUCCUCGUUUUAUCCUGAUGGUGGAGAUCAGGAAACUGCAAAGACUGGGAAGUUCUUAAAAAGGUUCACAGAUGAAGAGUCUAGAGUAUUCCUGCUUGAUAGGGGUAAUACCAGGGAUAAAGAGGCUUCAAAAGAGAAAGGAUCAGAGAAAGGGAGGGCAGAGGGAGAAUGGGAAGAUCAGGAAGCUCUAGAUUACUUCAGUGAUAAAGAGUCUGGAAAACAAAAGUUUAAUGAUUCAGAAGGGGAUGACACAGAGGAGACAGAGGAUUAUAGACAGUUCAGGAAGUCAGUCCUCGCAGAUCAGGGUAAAAGUUUUGCUACUGCAUCUCACCGGAAUACUGAGGAGGAAGGACUCAAGUACAAGUCCAAAGUUUCACUGAAAGGCAAUAGAGAAAGUGAUGGAUUUAGAGAAGAAAAAAAUGAUAAACAUAAAGAGACUGGAUAUGUGGUGGAAAGGCCUAGCACUACAAAAGAUAAGCACAAAGAAGAAGACAAAAAUUCUGAAAGAAUAACAGUAAAGAAAGAAACUCAGUCACCUGAGCAGGUAAAGUCUGAAAAGCUCAAAGACCUCUUUGAUUACAGUCCCCCUCUACACAAGAAUCUGGAUGCACGAGAAAAGUCUACCUUCAGAGAGGAAAGCCCACUUAGGAUCAAAAUGAUAGCGAGUGAUUCUCACCGUCCUGAAGUCAAACUCAAAAUGGCACCCGUUCCUCUUGAUGAUUCUAACAGACCUGCUUCCUUGACUAAAGACAGGCUGCUUGCUAGUACACUUGUCCAUUCUGUCAAGAAGGAGCAAGAAUUCCGAUCCAUCUUUGACCACAUUAAGUUGCCACAGGCCAGCAAAAGCACUUCAGAGUCAUUUAUUCAACACAUUGUGUCCUUGGUUCAUCAUGUUAAAGAGCAAUACUUCAAGUCAGCUGCAAUGACCCUAAGCGAGCGGUUCACUUCGUAUCAGAAAGCCACUGAAGAACAUAGUACUCGGCAAAAGAGCCCUGAAAUACACAGGAGAAUUGACAUCUCACCAAGUACCCUGAGGAAGGAUACCCGUUUAGCAGGGGAAGAGAGAGUUUUUAAAGAAGAAAAUCAAAAGGGAGAUAAAAAAUUAAGGUGUGACUCUGCUGACCUUCGACAUGACAUUGAUCACCGUAGAAAAGAAAGAAGUAAAGAACGGGGAGAUUCCAAGGGCUCCAGGGAAUCCAGGGGAUCAAGAAAGCAGGAAAAAACUCCGAAAGAUUACAAGGAAUACAAAUCUUACAAAGAUGACAGUAAACAUAAAAGAGAGCAAGAUCAUUCUCUAUCUUCAUCCUCUUCAGCAUCACCUUCUUCUCCCAGUUCUCGAGAAGAAAAGGAGAGUAAGAAGGAAAGAGAAGAAGAAUUUAAAACUCACCAUGAAAUGAAAGAAUACUCAGGCUUUGCAGGAGUUAGCCGACCACGAGGAACCUUUCAUGACGACAGAGAUGAUGGUGUGGAUUAUUGGGCCAAAAGAGGAAGAGGUCGUGGUACUUUUCAACGUGGCAGAGGGCGCUUUAACUUCAAAAAAUCAGGUAGCAGUCCUAAAUGGAAUCAUGACAAAUACCAAGGGGAUGGGAUUGUUGAAGAUGAAGAAGAGACCAUGGAAAAUAAUGAAGAAAAGAAGGACAGAUGCAAGGAAGAAAAGGAAUAAUAAAUAUGAAGUAAGAUUACAACAGAGCAGAACUUGCACCCACCGUUUUUUUUUUUACCUGAUUUUUGUUUUCAAAUAAGAAUGUAAGCAUUUUACUUAAAUUUUACUGUUUGCAAGUAGUCUAUAGA